AGUGGCCGCAGCAGCGCGCCGGGCCCUGGCCGCGCCCCAGCCGAGCGCAGCGCGGAGUCGCCCCGACCUUUCUCUGCGCAGUACGGCCGCCGGGACCGCAGCAUGGCGGGCAUCGCGGCCAAGCUGGCGAAGGACCGGGAGGCGGCCGAGGGGCUGGGCUCCCACGACAGGGCCAUCAAGUACCUCAACCAGGACUACGAGGCGCUGCGGAACGAGUGCCUGGAGGCCGGGACGCUCUUCCAGGACCCGUCCUUCCCGGCCAUCCCCUCGGCCCUGGGCUUCAAGGAGUUGGGGCCCUACUCCAGCAAAACCCGGGGCAUCGAGUGGAAGCGCCCCACGGAGAUCUGCGCUGACCCCCAGUUUAUCAUUGGAGGAGCCACCCGCACAGACAUCUGCCAAGGAGCCCUGGGUGACUGCUGGCUGCUGGCAGCCAUUGCCUCCCUCACCUUGAAUGAAGAAAUCCUGGCUCGAGUCGUCCCCCUAAACCAGAGCUUCCAGGAAAACUAUGCAGGGAUCUUUCACUUCCAGUUCUGGCAAUACGGCGAGUGGGUGGAGGUGGUGGUGGAUGACAGGCUGCCCACCAAGGACGGGGAGCUGCUCUUUGUGCAUUCAGCCGAAGGGAGCGAGUUCUGGAGCGCCCUGCUGGAGAAGGCAUACGCCAAGAUCAACGGAUGCUAUGAAGCGCUAUCAGGGGGUGCCACCACUGAGGGCUUCGAAGACUUCACCGGAGGCAUUGCUGAGUGGUAUGAGUUGAAGAAGCCCCCUCCCAACCUGUUCAAGAUCAUCCAGAAAGCUCUGCAAAAAGGCUCUCUCCUUGGCUGCUCCAUCGACAUCACCAGCGCCGCGGACUCGGAGGCCAUCACGUUUCAGAAGCUGGUGAAGGGGCACGCGUACUCGGUCACCGGAGCCGAGGAGGUUGAAAGUAACGGAAGCCUACAGAAACUGAUCCGCAUCCGAAAUCCCUGGGGAGAAGUGGAGUGGACAGGGCGGUGGAAUGACAACUGCCCAAGCUGGAACACUAUAGACCCAGAGGAGAGGGAAAGGCUGACCAGACGGCAUGAAGAUGGAGAAUUCUGGAUGUCUUUCAGUGACUUCCUGAGGCACUAUUCCCGCCUGGAGAUCUGUAACCUGACCCCAGACACUCUCACCAGCGAUACCUACAAGAAGUGGAAACUCACCAAAAUGGAUGGGAACUGGAGGCGGGGCUCCACCGCGGGAGGUUGCAGGAACUACCCGAACACAUUCUGGAUGAACCCUCAGUACCUGAUCAAGCUGGAGGAGGAGGAUGAGGACGAGGAGGAUGGGGAGAGCGGCUGCACCUUCCUGGUGGGGCUCAUUCAGAAGCACCGACGGCGGCAGAGGAAGAUGGGCGAGGACAUGCACACCAUCGGCUUUGGCAUCUAUGAGGUUCCAGAGGAGUUAAGUGGGCAGACCAACAUCCACCUCAGCAAAAACUUCUUCCUGACGAAUCGCGCCAGGGAGCGCUCAGACACCUUCAUCAACCUCCGGGAGGUGCUCAACCGCUUCAAGCUGCCGCCAGGAGAGUACAUUCUCGUGCCUUCCACCUUCGAACCCAACAAGGAUGGGGAUUUCUGCAUCCGGGUCUUUUCUGAAAAGAAAGCUGACUACCAAGCUGUCGAUGAUGAAAUCGAGGCCAAUCUUGAAGAGUUCGACAUCAGCGAGGAUGACAUUGAUGAUGGAUUCAGGAGACUGUUUGCCCAGUUGGCAGGAGAGGAUGCGGAGAUCUCUGCCUUUGAGCUGCAGACCAUCCUGAGAAGGGUUCUAGCAAAGCGCCAAGAUAUCAAGUCAGAUGGCUUCAGCAUCGAGACAUGCAAAAUUAUGGUUGACAUGCUAGAUUCGGACGGGAGUGGCAAGCUGGGGCUGAAGGAGUUCUACAUUCUCUGGACGAAGAUUCAAAAAUACCAAAAAAUUUACCGAGAAAUCGACGUUGACAGGUCUGGUACCAUGAAUUCCUAUGAAAUGCGGAAGGCAUUAGAAGAAGCAGGUUUCAAGAUGCCCUGUCAACUCCACCAAGUCAUCGUUGCUCGGUUUGCAGAUGACCAGCUCAUCAUCGAUUUUGAUAAUUUUGUUCGGUGUUUGGUUCGGCUGGAAACGCUAUUCAAGAUAUUUAAGCAGCUGGAUCCCGAGAAUACUGGAACAAUAGAGCUCGACCUUAUCUCUUGGCUCUGUUUCUCAGUACUUUGAAGUUAUAACUAAUCUGCCUGAAGACUUCUCAUGAUGGAAAAUCAGCCAAGGACUAAGCUUCCAUAGAAAUACACUUUGUAUCUGGACCUCAAAAUUAUGGGAACAUUUACUUAAACGGAUGAUCAUAGCUGAAAAUAAUGAUACUGUCAAUUUGAGAUAGCAGAAGUUUCACACAUCAAAGUAAAAGAUUUGCAUAUCAUUAUACUAAAUGCAAAUGAGUCGCUUAACCCUUGACAAGGUCAAAGAAAGCUUUAAAUCUGUAAAUAGUAUACACUUUUUACUUUUACACACUUUCCUGUUCAUAGCAAUAUUAAAUCAGGAAAAAAAAAUGCAGGGAGGUAUUUAACAGCUGAGCAAAAACAUUGAGUCGCUCUCAAAGGACACGAGGCCCUUGGCAGGGAAUAUUUAAAGCAACUUCAAGUUUAAAAUGCAGCUGUUGAUUCUACCAAACAACAGUCCAAGAUUACCAUUUCCCAUGAGCCAACUGGGAAACAUGGUAUAUCAUGAAGUAAUCUUGUCAAGGCAUCUGGAGAGUCCAGGAGAGAAGACUCACCUCUGUCGCUUGGGUUAAACAAGAGACAGGUUUUGUAGAAUAUUGAUUGGUAAUAGUAAAUCGUUCUCCUUACAAUCAAGUUCUUGACCCUAUUCGGCCUUAUACAUCUGGUCUUACAAAGACCAAAGGGAUCCUGCGCUUGAUCAACUGAACCAGUAUGCCAAAACCAGGCAUCCAAUUUGUAAACCAAUUAUGAUAAAGGACAAAAUAAGCUGUUUGCCACCUCAAAACUUUAUGAACUUCACCACCACUAGUGUCUGUCCAUGGAGUUAGAGGGGACAUCACUUAGAAGUUCUUAUAGAAAGGACACAAGUUUGUUUCCUGGCUUUACCUUGGGAAAAUGCUAGCAACAUUAUAGAAAUUUUGCCUUGUUGCCUUAUCUUCUUCCAAAUGUACUGUUAAAUAAAAAUAAAGGGUUACCCCAUGCAAUCACACCAUGCCAUGUUUUCCUUCCUGGAGGGCAGCCCCACAGGACGGUUUAUGAGCACACAAUUAUAGCUUGUUUCUACUUUAACAAGGUAUGCUGCCUCUGUAAAUUCAUGUAUUCAAAGGAAAAGACACCUUGCCUAUAAUUAAAAUGUGGAACUAUAAAAUUUUUUAAAAUCCAA